GAGUCGGGUCGUGGCUGCUGCCGGGUCCUGCGCGCUCCGGACUGAGGUGGCGUCCCUGGGCCGGACGGCGGUGUCCCGGCGUGGCGGGAAGCCGGCACUGGAGCGGGAGCGCACUGGGCGCGGGACCGGGAGGCGCAGGGACCGGACGGCUCCCGAGUCGCCCACCUGACGGUACCGAGAGGGCGGCGCCCCUCCGAGCAGAGCCGUCCCGGCCACUCCCCUGGGAUCUGACUUGGCUCUUGCGGUCGCGGGCACCGUGAAGCCCUGGGGUGUGCGUGGCUCCUCCUGGUAGGCGCCCUUUCCCGGCGUCCGGCUUGGGGUGGUGGUGGCGUUGACUCCAGCCCCGCCUCUCCCUGGAGAGGAGGGCUCCACUCGCUCCUUCGGCCUCCUCCCCUGGGGCCGCAGCGACUCGGGCCGGCUUCCUGCUUCCCUGCCUGCCGGCGGUCCCGCUGGCUAGAAGAAGUCUUCACUUCCCAGGAGAGCCAAAGCGUGUCUGGCCCUAGGUGGGAAAAGAACUGGCUGUGACCUUUGCCCUGACCUGGAAGGGCCCAGCCUUGGGCUGAAUGGCAGCACCCACGCCCGCCCGUCCGGUGCUGACCCACCUGCUGGUGGCUCUCUUCGGCAUGGGCUCCUGGGCUGCGGUCAAUGGGAUCUGGGUGGAGCUACCUGUGGUGGUCAAAGAGCUUCCAGAGGGUUGGAGCCUCCCCUCUUACGUCUCUGUGCUUGUGGCUCUGGGGAACCUGGGUCUGCUGGUGGUGACCCUCUGGAGGAGGCUGGCCCCAGGAAAGGACGAGCAGGUCCCCAUCCGGGUGGUGCAGGUGCUGGGCAUGGUGGGCACAGCCCUGCUGGCCUCUCUGUGGCACCAUGUGGCCCCAGUGGCAGGACAGUUGCAUUCUGUGGCCUUCUUAGCACUGGCCUUUGUGCUGGCACUGGCAUGCUGUGCCUCGAAUGUCACUUUCCUGCCCUUCUUGAGCCACCUGCCACCUCGCUUCUUACGGUCAUUCUUCCUGGGUCAAGGCCUGAGUGCCCUGCUGCCCUGCGUGCUGGCCCUAGUGCAGGGUGUGGGCCGCCUCGAGUGCCCGCCAGCCCCCAUCAACGGCACCCCUGGCCCCCCGCUCGACUUCCUUGAGCGUUUUCCCGCCAGCACCUUCUUCUGGGCACUGACUGCCCUUCUGGUCGCUUCAGCUGCUGCCUUCCAGGGUCUUCUGCUGCUGUUGCCGCCACCACCAUCUGUACCCACAGGGGAGUUAGGAUCAGGCCUCCAGGUGGGAGCCCCAGGAGCAGAGGAAGAGGUGGAAGAGUCCUCACCACUGCAAGAGCCACCAAGCCAGGCAGCAGGCACCACCCCUGGUCCAGACCCUAAGGCCUAUCAGCUUCUAUCAGCCCGCAGUGCCUGCCUGCUGGGCCUGUUGGCCGCCACCAACGCGCUGACCAAUGGCGUGCUGCCUGCCGUGCAGAGCUUUUCCUGCUUACCCUACGGGCGUCUGGCCUACCACCUGGCUGUGGUGCUGGGCAGUGCUGCCAAUCCCCUGGCCUGCUUCCUGGCCAUGGGUGUGCUGUGCAGGUCCUUGGCAGGGCUGGGCGGCCUCUCUCUGCUGGGCGUGUUCUGUGGGGGCUACCUGAUGGCGCUGGCAGUCCUGAGCCCCUGCCCGCCCCUGGUGGGCACCUCGGCGGGGGUGGUCCUCGUGGUGCUGUCGUGGGUGCUGUGUCUUGGCGUGUUCUCCUACGUGAAGGUGGCAGCCAGCUCCCUGCUGCAUGGCGGGGGCCGGCCGGCAUUGCUGGCAGCCGGCGUGGCCAUCCAGGUGGGCUCUCUGCUCGGCGCUGUUGCUAUGUUCCCCCCGACCAGCAUCUAUCACGUGUUCCACAGCAGAAAGGACUGUGCAGACCCCUGUGACUCCUGAGCCUGGGCAGGUGGGGACCCCGCUCCCCAACACCUGUCUUUCCCUCAAUGCUGCCACCAUGCCUGAGUGCCUGCAGCCCAGGAGGCCCGCACACCGGUACACUCGUGGACACCUACACACUCCAUAGGAGAUCCUGGCUUUCCAGGGUGGGCAAGGGCAAGGAGCAGGCUUGGAGCCAGGGACCAGUGGGGGCUGUAGGGUAAGCCCCUGAGCCUGGGACCUACAUGUGGUUUGCGUAAUAAAACAUUUGUAUUUAA